AUUCCUUGCUACAGAGCCCUGUUGUCCACGGUUUAUUUUUUUCCACAGGACGAUUCUUAAUACUUUACCAGAUGGAAACACCACCACCACCAUCUUUGCCAUUUCAGCUCUUAUGCAUUAGGCAGCCACGAUAUCUUCAGGGCCUUCUUUCUCAUUCACGCCAUCUCAAGACACAGCAAGACCAACCCCUCCCCUUCCUCCUUCUUUUCAACCUACUUAACCUGAAAUCGAUGAUGAAGACAUUUGUGAUGAUCCACAUCCACUUAAUGAAAGCAAGGCAAGGUACUUCUACGGAAGGGUGCGACCUCACGGAUGGAGCAAUGGUCACUCAGUCUGAGGUAUUUUGUUAUGGUAGCCUGAACAGACCAAGACACCAAUAAGACGGUAUUUGGAGGUGG